GCACACACACAUAAUAUACUAUUGUCAACACUAGGUUUUAUUUUUAAAAAUCUUUACCAUUUGAUAAGUGGUAAAUAUUACUUAAUCUUAAUAUGCCUCAUUACAGUGAUAUUGAAUGUUUUUUCAUAUCAUCAGUGGCGUUUGUAUUGCCUUUUUUUCUACUUCUUUUGGUAAAUUGUGUCUUUUACUCAUUUAAUUAUUUUCUUACUGGUUUGAAAAAGCUCUUUAAAUAUUAAGGGUGUUAGUCUUUUGUCUUAAAUAUGUCACAAUAUGUAUGGAAAUAAUUAGCAGUAUAUAACAACAUCAAAUUGCUACCAAUGUUGAUAUAAAAAUUGUUCAUUUCAUAGGUUAAUUUUUUUUAAUCCUUUGGUUUCUAAUGAUAUUGGUUAAUUCAUUUGUUAACUGCUAUUUUCUGUAGCUACUUGAAAGUUCUUAUCUGACUGUAUCGUAAAUCAGCAUGCUUUCAGCUGUAUAUGUCUAGGAAAUUGACAUUUACUUUAAUACUUAAUAAAAAAAUAUGUUGGAGAAAAGCAGUGUAUUCUGGAGUCAAAUACAUGAUUUUGGGUGGGUGACGUAAUCGGCUACUGUCCUCCUUUUCUAGAUAGCCAAGAUUUUUGAAGCAUUUAACAUCCCUGAAAGGCAGGACUAAUGCUAUGUCUACCAUGCACUGCUAAUUCUGACACUUUGACCUAAUGGAUAAAUGCCAGUACAGUGGGUCUAGCCAGUUAGCUUGGUCAGAGAACAAGAUGACUAAGAUUCUCUCCCCCUUUCCUCACCAAAUUGAUUAGUUGUAGGACAGAACUGACUGAAGCAACCUGUUGUUUUGGCAACCCAUGGACACCACCUGUUUCUUCCAUUCCUCCGUCCAGCCUCUCACUGCCCUAGUGCAGUGCUGUGUGCAUAGUGGGUAGGAGAUCAAUGUUGUUGCUAAAGAAAGUAGCAAUAAAGAAGAGUAGAUUGCUUUUUUUCCAAGCUUUUGUGUUUUUAAGGCACCCCGCUGGUUUUGACAUUCGUUGCUCCAGCUGAACUGCUCUAUGCUGAAGCCCUGCAGGUCUCAAGUGUUUGGUUCAGAGUAAUUUCAGGCCAUAUGAAUGCUUUCUUAAGUAUCAUUGGAAUUUACUGGGCUGGCUGUCUGCCAGCUAUUACCAUAUUUAGCAUGAAGAGACCUGGGGAAUGAGGACAUUUCUGAUCAACCAAGGAAGGAAACCUAUUUGAAGGAUUACAAUAUUUUCUUUUUUUUUUUUUAAUGGUGUAGUUCAGAAAACGCCAGUUAGACUGAGACUCAGAUUUAUGUCCACUGGUCUUUGUUUCUGUGCCCCAUCCCAAAAUUAAUUUAUGAAUAGGAAAAGAGAUUUGAUAGUGAAGUUCUUUCUCACUCUGAAGUCUAAUACUGUUUCUGGGAGGAAGUAAGAGAAUUAUUAUGCCCACACUGUGCACUGAGAGGCUUAACCAGCAGGUGAAGCUGUUGAUUAAAAACAUAGGUUGAUGAGUAUUCUCAUUUUUCUCCUUUGAAGCUUUCAGAAAUUUUCUGCUUUGUCCUGGUCUAAAUUUAUUUUGGCCCAGCCCUUGUCUCCACCCUACAUUUCAAACCAGUAGCCUUCCCUCUAUGGCUCAACAUUUCUCUGCCUCAGUUUUUUCCAUUUUAAAGAUGAAGAUAUUGUUUGGAAGGACCAGUAAAUACAAUUAAUAUAAAAAUUGCUUCUGUAGAAUCAAACAACCUCCAACAUUUCUGUUGGAAAUUUAUAGUUUAUAGAGUAUUCUUACACAAUGAUCUCCUUUAAUCCUCACAAACUUGGUGGAAAUGGAGCCUCACAGGGGCUAGGUGACUUGUAUACAUUGUUUACCCCUACAUAAUAAGUGACAGAGCUGGUACUUAAACUUGUGGCUUGAUUUUUCUUUUUUUUUUUGAGUUGGAGUUUUGCUCUUGUUGCCCAGGCUGGAGUGCAAUGGCGCAAUCUCGGCUCACCGCAACCUCCACCUCCCGGGUUCAAGUGAUUCUCCUGCCUCAGCCUCCCGAGUAGCUGGAAUUACAGGCAUGCACCACAACGCCUGGCUAAUUUUUUGUAGUUUUAGUAGAGACGGGGUUUCUCUAUGUUGGGCAGGCUGGUCUCGUACUCCUGACCUCAGGUGAUCCGCCCGCCUCAGCCUCCCAAAGUGCUGGGAUUACAGGUGAGCCACCGUGCCUGGUCCUUGCAGCUUGAUUUUUUAAACAUCAGAUUUUUUUUUCUUUUUUGAUUUUUAUUAUUAUGUGUCUGUCAUUCUGCUAGGGGCUUUGCAAAUAUUGCUUUAUUUAAUUCAUAUGGCUAUCCUUUGGAGUAGACAAUAUUUUUCUACAUUAUAGGUAAGGAAUUUGGAACUUAGGUUCACAGCUUUGGAUGUUGGCCUAUGGUUAGUGAGGGGUGUAGCCAGGAUUCAAACCCCUGUCUGGCUCUAGGGCCGCUGCAAUAAAUCAUGGUGUUUUAUGUACAUUCAUACACUUAACACUUUGCAACAACCCUAAGAGACAGGGGUAGGUAUUUAGGGAAACUGGGGCUUCUAACUUGCACAGGAUAAUGCAAUUAGUAAGUGGCUUAGUCGAGAUUCAGAGCUAGAUCUGUCUCCAUAACCCUCACUCAUUCCAGGAUACUGCAGAUGCCUAUUUUUAUGAUAUGUAUAAGUAAAAAUUAAUUUAAAAAACUACCUUCUUUGAAGGGUCAGCCAGUUAGAACUCUUUUGUAUCUUCUGAAUAAGUAAGAAGUGGAUGGACAUUAGCUGACCGAUACAUUGAUGGCUUUUAACCUUCUAUCAGUUGAUUUCCAUUACCAGGACAAGCAAAUAUAAUUUGGAGGGAAAAGAGGGGAGUUUCCAUUAAGGAUGAAUCUUUAAGCCGAAAAGGGCCACAGUGAUGAACUCUUCAGAGGACUGCUCUCAGGAGCAAUGGCCCUUCUCCUCUGGGCUCUGCUUGGGGCAUUCCUGUUUGUAUUUAUGGAGACAUCUUUUUGAAAGGCAGAUGCCAGCUUUGGUGGGGAGAAGGUUGGAAAACAUACAAGCCUUGCUCUAAAUUUACUAGCCCCGUGUCUUUGGGCUAGUUUCUGAAGCAUGGUGUGCCUCAAUUUUAUUAUUUUAAAAAUAAAGAUAGUAGCAGUAUAUUUUGGAGUUGUUAUGAAGAUAAUAUCAGUUAAUAAAUGUUAGAUUCAUUGGACAGUACCAGGCACAUAGUUAAAGUGCAGUAAAUAGUAGUUAUUGUUGGUAUUGGUGUUAUUUUAUGUUGCAGUACAGACUGGCUUCUUGGUGCAUUCACUUUUCUUUAAUCAAAAGUGGAUGAGUGAUUGGGAACCUUCAUGAGGAAAUAGGAACAUCAUCUUUGCAGCCUGUGGAUUGUUCACUGGUUUCCUGUGAUCUAAUAAUUAUUUAAGGGUUUCAUAUUUGAGUCUUUUCCCUUAAUGAGGUACACUUUCAGUUUGGGGAGAUUUUAUCUAUAGGCAUACCUUAUUUUAUUUUGUGUUCCCUUUUAUUGUGCUUCACAGAUUUUGUUUUAUUUUUUACAAAUUGAAAGUUUGUGGCAACCCUAUGUCGAGCAAAUGUAUCAGCACCAUUUUUUCCAAUAGCAUAUACUCACUAUAUGUCCCUGUGUCAGUAUUUUUUAGCAAUAAAGUAUUUUUAAACUCAGGUAUAUGCAUUAUGCUUUAGACAUAAUGCUGUUGCAUGCUUAAUGGACUAGAGUAUACUGUAAACAUAACUUUUGUAUGCACUGGGGAACCAAAAAAUUUCUGACUUGCUUCAUUGUACUGUUUGCUUUAUUGAGGUGAGCUGGAGCUGAAGCCACAAUAUCACAAAGGUAUGCUUGUAUUAUGCAAGUUGCAUUGAUAGGUGUUAAAUCAUUUUCCCAAUUUUUAUUAACCACACAUUUGUGAUUGGAUGUUAUGUUUAGUAAAGAUAUUGUGAUUUUCUGAGGUACAGCUUUGAGAACAGUAUCAGGUCUAACACUCUUGUUUCCAAAUUUCCUAUGAUAUGACAAACAUAAUCACAUGCCAUCCAGUGUCACCAUGCAGAGUACUAAUGUGAAGCCAAAAUACUUGGUGUUUUAAUUAGCCUUAAAGCAGUUAAUGAACUAUCUCUGUUAGACAUUUUGAAAUAAUAAAAAUAUCCCAUUGUCUUUUAUUACAACCUCAGGGGCUCCUGGAGAUUUUGGGAUCUUGUGUGGGGAACCACCCAUCUAAUCCAUCCUUGUUUUAAAGAGAGAAAACCAAAGAAGCAAAGUGACUGGCCCAAGUACCUAGAGCUGGGUCAGGGUUGGGGCCAGAAUCCAAUCUCUUGACUUUUAGUCAAGUGAUUUUUCCACUAUGCUCAGUACUCAAAUUAUGUAUCAAUAUGUCGGCCCUUGUUUUUUGAGGUCUGAAAAGGGUUAGUGCCAGUCAACAACAGUAGAGGAGUAGAAAGGGUGUUGGGAUGGGAGAGGUGUGGCUAUAUUUAAAAUUUCAAUGACAGCAGUGAAAAUAAUUUGCCUGUGAACCUCUGCCUGUCCCUUUGGACUUCUUUGUAGUAGUUGAGACAGCCCGGCAGGUCUGGUGUCAUUAGUGAUUCAGAAUUGGAUUAACCUGGACUGGUGGAGUUACUUUCUCAGAAAAGGGCUUUAUAUUUUAACAUUUGUUUCCCUUGACAGUUUGCUUCUUCUCAAGUUUUGGCAGCCUUGAACAAGUGGUUGUCAGGUUUUUAUUUUGUUUUGUUUUAAGAAAAAAUUCCAAAUUUUAUUUUGCCGAUUUAGUAAGUUAUCCUCUACCUGCCACUCCCUUCUGCUCCCUCUAUAAUUAUUUCUAAGACUUUAUUUUUCCAUUGUGGGAACAUUAUGGAAGGUUUUCUUUUACAGUCUGAGAUAUUUAUAAUUAUGUGUAAGCACACAGUUUAUAGAAUAUGUAAAUGGUCCAUAUGUUAACUUAAAUACCCUUAAAAUAUUUUCCAAUAAUUUAAAUCUUUCCAUAAAAGUAGCUGAAGCUGCUUAUAAUAAAAGAGAAGUAUACACGAAGGAUAGCAGAAUUUGGAUGUAGUUAAUAUAGAUAAAUAUGAAUGUCACUUUGGAGGAACUGGAAGUAUUUGCAUGAAUACUGAUCAAGUCAUGCCUCCUUGUUAAUAGAGUGAACAAAACAGAUGAAUGUUUCUGUUUUCAUGAAGUUUAUGUGACUAUCAGUAGCUUCCAUAUUCUGAGGGUUUAUUAUGUGACAGAUGCUUGGGGACAAAAUACUUUACUUGUUUCCUUUAGUCCUUAAAAUAGAUGUUAGGAUUCUUGUUUACAGAAAAGUUAAGGAAUGUUCAUCCAGAUCACCUAGCCAGUCAGUGGUAAAGAACAGUCACUGGAACCCCUCUUUCCUGAUCCAAAGCCAACAUACUUAACCAUAAUAAAUAAUGCCAUUGUCUGGUGGAAUCCUGUAGUCCCUUAGAUAGUGUAAUUUUGUAUUUAAUGUAAACAUUUUGUGCACUAAACUGACUUACAUUUUACUUUUUAAAACAAUAUUUUAAUUCUGAAUGAACAUUUGCAUAAUAGGAGAAUGAUCUAAAUUGCAAACUUCCAUUUUGAAGAGUUGUAGUUCUUUUAAAUCUUUUUGUAACUGGGAAGAAGAAUGGAAUUAUGUUUGUUGUAAUCCAAGGAAAGUUGGUUAGCAUUCUUUCCUGUUACUUUUUGAUCCCAAAAGAAAUUCUUUAGUAGAUUAAGACCAGGAAUGAAUGUGUGGAUUUUUUUAAAUAAAAAAUUGAGAGAGAUUGCAACUAGCAAUUCAGAGCCAGAUUUAUGUUCAGAAAUGUUUGAUGCCAGCCGUUUUAGUUACAAAUAGCUUUUUCUUGACUGUACAGUUGUGUUCUUAUGGUACCAUUCUGAAAGUGAUGUAAGAGACCAUGUAAAAUGAUUGGAAUGCCUCAGCAUCUGAACAAUGCACAUAGCCAAUUAUUAAAAUUACCCAGUACUAACCUGUCUUGGCUUAGGAACUAUGAAAUUAACUGUGGGUAGCAUUUCUACACAUAUCAUUACAGAACAAGCAUAAAGACAAGCUUGUUUUUUUCCUUUUCUGUGGAUUUGUUUUUUCUUAUUACCAUAUCUUUUGUUACUGAAAACUGGUGGUCAUCUGUACUAAUAGAUAAGAGAAGUGUGUUUGACACCAAUACCUAAUCUUAGAUUAUCCCUGCUAUUUUAAAACACAGUCCUUCGCCUGCAUGCUCAGACAUGUGGGUUCUUUCAAACAUACUGGACUUCCUCCUUAGGUUUUAGUUGUGUUAGUCAAUAGUUGAAUGUUGAAGGAGAGGAUGCCAAGGGAUAUUAAAGAAGGUAAAAGAGAUAAGUGACAGCAAACAUUAUUUAUUUUUAAUUAUCUCUCAGAAUGACUUUUAGAUACCCUUCCCUACUACCUUUUGAUUUUUGCUUUAGCAUAGCUGGUGAGUUUUGGAAUCAGAGAGACUGGGCUCUGAUUUGUACUAGCUAAGAAUAUUAGACAAGCCACUUAACUUCUUUAAGUCUCAGUACCCGUAUUUAUAUAAUGGGAAUAAUAGUAAUAUCUAACUUGCAGGAUUGUUUGUAAAGAUUGAAAGCAACAUAUUUAAUUGUGCUUGCGUGGUUCUGGGCACAGAAUAGGCACCCGAGUGUAGGGGCCCCUGAACUUUAAAGUUCAUUACUUUCAUGGUAAUUCCUCCUUUGGAAUAUAUAGCCUGGGAACAUUUGUCUCUAGACCUUGUUUCAGUUUCUUUUAAUGACUCCCUUUAGGCUCUGCUUCAUGGCCAAUGCAAGAUUAUGGAUCACCUAAAGAGUAGACUAAAAGUACUAUUGUCUAGUAACUUCAAGUUUGUAGGUUAACUCACUGUGAAUCAAAAGCUUUUAAAAAUCUUUUGUGUGGUCAUAGUUUGUAGUGUCUUGUACCUCUCAUCUCAGAAGCAAUUGAUUCAUAGAAAAAAUUAUUUAGGAUUUCAGAUUAAAGAUGAAGAACUCUUUCAAUAAGAAGGAACUGAUUUGGUUGGAUUAUUUGUUUCUUUCACCCCUGAGUUUUCAUGGAAAUCAGGUUUAAAAGGUUAGAAGCAGUUGGUUUUCAGCAUUGGGAAAGCUUAUCUGAUCAGGCAUGCGAAGUGGCCUAUGUCGGAUUUCUGAGCUAGGAAAGGCUAGGGGAGGUUGAGGAGAUUAUUGUACUUGUAAUUCCUGAGCAUGGUUGAGACACAAGGAGAGGAUUGUGGAAAUUGUUUUUAAAAAAUUGUUGAAGUUAAUGCAUUCUUGGGUGGAUUUGCAAAACAGAACAAAACAAAAAGUUGUUGAAGUUAGUUACACUGGUCUAACAACGUAUACUUACCACCCCCAUUUGGGCUGGAGGAAUGGAUCUAAUAAUAAUAUAGGUGUUUGUGAUCUAAUUUGAAUCAUGUAAUCAUUUAUCAUUUCUGGGUUAGAUGGUAAGGAUUUUCUGUUUCACAGAUUUUUAGACUGGGAAUUGUGCUAUUAUAAAAUAAUAUUUUACAUUAAAUAAUGCUAUCUAGGUUGUAAUCACCUUAAUAGACAUGAUUUAUUUGGGCCACAAAUGAACUCUGGUAAGAAUGGAGGGCUGGUUACAUUAUUUUAGUUUUACAGAUGAAAAUAAUCAGUCUCAAAUAGCUUAAGGGAAUUCCUUUAGACCAUAUGGUUAGUAUAUGGAAAAGCCAGAGCUAGAACCCAGGUUCUGAUUUCCAGAGCAGUUCUUAUUUCAUGAUACCGCAUAAUUUUAUAAUGUCCCUAAAUCCGAAUUUCAUUUCUCAUGAUGUGAAAGGAUUCUCUUUAUUUCUGUUUGGUUAGCUGCAUCAGAGCAUGACAGAAAUGGAGCAGAAUUUGAGUAUUCUUUCCCCAGAUGGGUCAGUUAGCUUUUCUUAAAGCUAUUCUGUGCUUACAUUGUUAAUCAGUUGUCCCUGGUUCCUAGACAGGAUGUUGAUACAUGUGAAAUAGGCAGGAAUAUGUGUCUGACUCAGCUUAACUCAUCACAACUUUCAUAUGUCCUGCUAGUGGGUCUAUAACGUCACCCUCGUUUACAGGCGUUUUUAAUUUUCUGAUGUCUAUUUCUUAGUAUUUUUCCUCAGCCAUUUUUAAUGUCUCAAGCCGUAGUUCUUCCUGAGUGGCCUGAAGUGAUUUUGCUGCUCUUUAAAGCUUCCUUAAGGUUUUUCAAGAGCGUACAACAUAGGCUGCUUCUAAGUGUAUUUUUAUUUCCUAGCUCUUAGCAUUUCUCACCUUAUCAUUAUAACUUUAAAUUUAAACAGAAUACAAAUUGUGUACACAGAUGGUGUGUCACUAUUGCACUGUCACUUAUGUAAGUGCAGUUUAGCAUUUCUUCUUUCCUUUUAAUCAAAAUGAGGAAAUAGAAAAUGUUUUGUUAUGGUAGUUUUACACAUACACCCACAAGGAAAUGUGUAUCUAGAGUCUGUGGGAACUGUGACUGAUACAUUUCAGGGAAUAAAAUGUAUGAUGGCUAAAAUUUUAACUCUGCCAAAUGUUCACGGGGAAAGAAAAAUUAACAAACUCACAUUUUACACUUUAUUUUAGCCUAGUCUCUGCCUUGUUUACAUCUAUAUGAUAAUGAAGCUAUACUUGUCUUUCCACAACAGUGUAUUUUAUAAGUUGUACCUUUUGUUUAAGGGAGCCUUCUUAACAAACUUUCUUUCAGUUGUCCAGUGUACAGAAGCUUACUGGAAGGAGUGGCCAACUAGUUAAAGGUUUGACACCUCAAUAUCAACAAAAUGCCAAGUGGAUCAUUUUGACUCUCACAGCAAUCCAACUGGACAUUUGACCAUGCCCCGUGGUCAGUGGAGAGCUUCUUCUCUGAAGGCCACUUUUAUCUAGCACAUCAAGGCUAUACAUCUCUUUCACUAAGAAGAAUUUGGCACUUUUAUGUUGUGAGAGCUGAGAUUCACCAUUCUCCACCAUCCUGAGAAGAGCUUUGAUAGAAGGGCUACUCGUGAGCAUUGCAGUGUCGAGAUGGCUAUGAACCCUGUGUAAAUGAAGGAAUGUGUGUUACCUACCACAAUGGCACAGGAUACUGCAAAUGUCCAGAAGGCUUCUUGGGGGAAUAUUGUCAACAUCGAGACCCCUGUGAGAAGAACCGCUGCCAGAAUGGUGGGACUUGUGUGGCCCAGGCCAUGCUGGGGAAAGCCACGUGCCGAUGUGCCUCAGGGUUUACAGGAGAGGACUGCCAAUACUCGACAUCUCAUCCAUGCUUUGUGUCUCGACCUUGCCUGAAUGGCGGCACAUGCCAUAUGCUCAGCCGGGAUACCUAUGAGUGCACCUGUCAAGUCGGGUUUACAGGUAAGGAGUGCCAAUGGACCGAUGCCUGCCUGUCUCAUCCCUGUGCAAAUGGAAGUACCUGUACCACUGUGGCCAACCAGUUCUCCUGCAAAUGCCUCACAGGCUUCACAGGGCAGAAGUGUGAGACUGAUGUCAAUGAGUGUGACAUUCCAGGACACUGCCAGCAUGGUGGCAUCUGCCUCAACCUGCCUGGUUCCUACCAGUGCCAGUGCCUUCAGGGCUUCACAGGCCAGUACUGUGACAGCCUGUAUGUGCCCUGUGCACCCUCGCCUUGUGUCAAUGGAGGCACCUGUCGGCAGACUGGUGACUUCACUUUUGAGUGCAACUGCCUUCCAGGUAAGGAGCUCCCUAGUGUCCCAGGAUUAGGGGACAAACCCCUAGCACAGGAGGUAGUGGGUGUGGCUCAAUUGCUUUUUUUAGGAAGCGCAAGGAAAAAGGGAAGUGAGAAUUUUGUGUGGGGUGGGUUGCUAGUGAGGGAGGAGUUUUAUGGGCCCACUGUGGUCCAUAAACUGAGCAGGGGAUAAUUUAGCAUGUCAGGGUUUAUGAUGAUGAGUGGCUAGAAAAUUGUUUAUUGUCCCUUUUGUAGAAACAGUGAGAAGAGGAACAGAGCUCUGGGAAAGAGACAGGGAAGUCUGGAAUG